AAACGUGCUCACCCGACGGCAGCUCACAGGACCCCGGAGAGUCCUGGCAUGGUAUCUCGGUCCGGACUCUCCGCUGGGCCCACGAAGGAGAAAGGCUGCCUCGGAUUCCUGCGCCCAAGCCAAGGUCCGGCGCCCACGGAGGCAAGUCCGGUCUCACGGUGACCUCCCGCCGGCGCCGCCUUCGCCGCCAACCAUCCAGUUCUUCCUCCAGGCCACGUUCUCCUGCGUGGUCGCUGCCUCCUGCAGAGUGGCCAGCAAUAGCUGCUGGGUCCUGGCCGCCUCCUCCCUGCUCCUUGGGUCCUGCAGUGGCAUCUCCUGAGGGCAGGAAGGGGAGUUCGCAGGAGCUCCAGUCCGGGGCUCUCCACCCGCCCACCCUUCCUCGGGACUACCAGUUGCUUCUACCUUUAGCAUUUCCUGCUUCCGCCGCUCUCCCGGGGUCACGAUAACGAGGAGCGCGUAGCCCACGCCAGCCCCUGCGCCCAGCAUUGCGACUGAGAUCAGCAUUUUCCGCAAGGAAUCCAUGGCCGCCUGCACAGCCAGCGGAGCGCCCACGGGAGCUCCCCGCAGCCGCAAGCUGUUGCCGCGCGGUCUCACUACCCCUUGGCGCAGGCUAGAGCGCCCUAUAGCAGAAACCAUAGAUAAGCGGCCGGCUAGAGAGGACCUGCUCGAGGAAACGUUUGGAAUCCGGAGCGCUUGGAUCUCAGGUUUAGCUGAGGGGGUUGAGGUGUCCAAGAAGUGCUGGCACCAAGGGCUGAGCGCGGGGACCCUGUGUCCUCAAUUCCGGGGUGGGAUUGCUAGGGGGAGAGUGCGUGUCUUCAUGGUUGCCGUGGGUUUUAUGAUUGCCCAUUUUUCUGUCUUCCGACGUUUCCCGAUCAGUAGAGGCCCGAGCUGUGCUCUGUGGUUUCCUGCAGUCACCCGCGCGUUUUCAACACAGCGCAUGGAGGGCAUCUACACACAUACACAUCCCUCUCCAUCCCCUCAACUCUGGAACAAACACUCAAAGUCAAGUAUACUGGUUGGAGAAAUGGUGUCUCCAGGGAGUAAGUAGAAAUAAAGAUCCUAUCUCACCUCUUGGGCAUUUUCCCCUCCCCUGAAAGCGUAUAAUCGCUUAGCACAGUCGGUGCUUAAGGGGCCAGGCUCCAAAGAAGAUUAAAGGAACAGUUUGUGGGGUGCACUGGGCAGCAGUACUCUCCUCUGAGUUCAAUCAUCUUGCACUCUAAGAAUCACCACCAUGGCCCUUGUGCCAGGGAGAAGCAAGGAGGAUGGGCUUUGGACUAGAAAUAGCCCAGGCUCCUCCCAGCAUCCAGAAAGUCCCAGGCUGCCCAACCCUCUCUGGGACAGAGGAAAAAUUGGCAAGGUUGAAGGUCACCAGCACAUUCAGGAUUUCUCUCAAAAGUCCCAUCUGCCGUCUAUUGUGGUGGAAUCCAGUGAGGUGAAUGAAGAGAGUGGGGAUCUCCAUUUGCCCCAUGAGGAGCUGCUGCUGCUCACUGAUGGUGAGGAAGAGGAUGCUGAGGCCUUCUUCCAAGACCAAAGUGAAGAGCCAGGCUGGGCUUGGAGCCCACAGGACCCUAGAAGUCCUUUAAGAACAUUUAACGCUGGACUCAGCUGGGGGCAGGACCAGGAUGAAGAAGAUGCUUGUUGGAUUCUUGAGGACACAGCAUGUCUGGAAGCCACCAACCACUGUCCCUUCUGGGACUCAACAGGCUCCCGUGUUUGUAGAAGUGGCUUUGUGGAAUAUUCCCAUCUCCUGCCUCCUAAUAGCUUUGAGGGAGCUGAAGAAGAAGCUGUUCAAACGCCGGCGGGUGUUGAAUCGGGAGCGGCGUCUGAGGCACCGGGUGGUCGGGGCUGUGAUAGACCAAGGGCUGAUCACGCGGCACCACCUCAAGAAGCGGGCGUCCAGUGCACGUGCCAACAUUACACUGUCAGGGAAGAAGCGCAGAAAACUCCUCCAGCAGAUCCGGCUUGCCCAGAAAGAGAAGACAGCCAUGGAAGUGGAAGCCCCUUCAAAGCCAGCCAGGACUAGUGAACCACAGCUCAAAAGGCAAAAGAAGACAAAAGCCCCCCAGGAUGUAGAAAUGAAGGACCUUGAAGAUGAGAGCUAAACCUCUUCCACUAGAAGAUUCUCAACUGGAGCCAGCCUUCAGACUCAGUGGUUGUUUCAGAGGACUUUGACAAAAGCAAGGCCCCUUUUCACUCUCCAGAUUUCCUCCUACCUAAUGGCCUACUGACCUCCCCUAGAGGGAUGUCUUUGGGAGGGAAGAAGGUACAGAAGAAAGAUUGGAGAAGGGCCUCUCUAGCAGUCAACUCCAUUUGUAAUAAAGCCCUAGCACUCUGA